AGUACUGGGUGCAGCCUGAUGGCGCAGGAGGUAGACACGGCACAGGGCGCCGAGAUGCGGCGGGGCGCGGGCGCGGCUCGGGGACGCGCUUCCUGGUGCUGGGCCCUGGCGCUGCUUUGGCUCGCGGUGGUUCCGGGCUGGUCCCGGGUCUCGGGCAUCCCCUCCCGGCGCCACUGGCCGGUGCCCUACAAGCGCUUUGACUUCCGUCCAAAACCUGAUCCUUAUUGUCAAGCUAAGUAUACUUUCUGUCCAACUGGCUCACCUAUCCCAGUUAUGGAGGGUGAUGAUGACAUUGAAGUUUUUCGAUUACAAGCCCCAGUAUGGGAAUUUAAAUAUGGAGACCUCCUGGGACACUUGAAAAUUAUGCAUGAUGCCAUUGGAUUCAGAAGUACAUUAACUGGCAAGAACUACACAAUGGAAUGGUAUGAACUUUUCCAACUUGGCAACUGUACAUUUCCCCAUCUCCGACCUGAAAUGGAUGCCCCUUUCUGGUGUAAUCAAGGCGCUGCCUGCUUUUUUGAGGGAAUUGAUGAUGUUCACUGGAAGGAAAAUGGGACAUUAGUUCAAGUAGCAACUAUAUCAGAUGGAGAAACUGAGGCACAGAGAGGUUAAAGUUACACAGCUUAGAAACAUGUUCAACCAAAUGGCAAAGUGGGUGAAACAGGACAAUGAAACAGGAAUUUAUUAUGAGACAUGGAAUGUAAAAGCCAGCCCAGAAAAGGGGGCAGAGACAUGGUUUGAUUCCUACGACUGUUCCAAAUUUGUGUUAAGGACCUUUAACAAGUUGGCUGAAUUUGGAGCAGAGUUCAAGAACAUAGAAACCAACUAUACAAGAAUAUUUCUUUACAGUGGAGAACCUACUUAUCUGGGAAAUGAAACAUCUGUUUUUGGGCCAACAGGAAACAAGACUCUUGGUUUAGCCAUAAAAAGAUUUUAUUACCCCUUCAAACCACAUUUGCCAACUAAAGAAUUUCUGUUGAGUCUCUUGCAAAUUUUUGAUGCAGUGAUUGUGCACAAACAGUUCUAUUUGUUUUAUAAUUUUGAAUAUUGGUUUUUACCUAUGAAAUUCCCUUUUAUUAAAAUAACAUAUGAAGAAAUCCCUUUACCUAUCAGAAACAAAACACUCUCUGGUUUAUAAAACACCUUAAUUCUACUGCUCUUUUUUCUCCAAUCACCAGCAUCUGUUUUUCAGGGGGUGAUUUUACUUUUGUGAAUUCCUUAGCCUUUCUUCCUUGGUGCAUAAAGUUAAAAUGCACAUCAGCAGAAUUGCUGCAUAUUAACAUCUCAGGACUCUUCUCUUGUAAAGAAGCUGAAAUUCGUACUAUAUUGGCCAAAGUGAGCGAGUUAGGUGAUCUUGGUUUCAAUUUCCGAGCCUUUGUUAAUAUGGAGAAUUAUGGUUCAUAUCAGUUAUGUAGGACCUUUGGACCCAGGGUCCUACAGAUAGAUAUGGUGUGCCCAGAUUUUAAAAAUACCUUCAAAAAUAAAAAAUACAUUCAGUGACAUUUUCAUGGUGGGAGCUCUUCUUUCUGAUAUGGCAGUUACACUUUUUCACUUAAGUGCUUUAGUUUAGACUAACUUUACAACUUCUAUAACUUUUGGAACCAAGUUUAGUAUAGUCUGAUUACAUUCCAUUCACCUAACUUUAGACAUUCGUUUAGACACCAUAACUGGAGUGAUUGUGCUUCUAGAUGUGGCAAAUCCAGUGUUAACACAUAUUUCUGGCUGAGAUUUUGGAACUAGCUAGUAACUGGCUUGUGUUCUUUAAGCAUACUAACAUCACUAAAUCUUAGGAUUUAGGAUUGCUGUAAAGAUGUAAGUUGUGUAUGUUUGGCAGGUCACAUUGAAUGGCAGUGAUAAUGAUUAAUCAAAGAACAAAUGUCAUCCUUGAUCUUGCCUAAUGUAGUUUAUGUGCCAAACUUUCCAGGGUUUUGUAGUCACCUAGAUUUUAAGCUGAUAGCAUAGUGCUUCAGCGGUUCUUCUAACCGGGGUAUGCAGGAACAUGGCUGCAGACACGUUUGGGUAAACAGGCACCUUCUGACUUCUUCAUUGUUUCCUGUAGUUCUCCCUCUUCCCACAAAGCUGUCAGCGCAGUGGAAGAGGUUGCACUUCUCCGAGAGAGGACAGGUUUCUGUUAAGAUCACCAAGUAGCUGUGCUUUAAUUAGAGCCAGACAAGCUUUCAAGGUCCUUUAAGUAUUUGAUGAUCAACUGAACACGUUUCUAUUCAAGGAGAAAACACCAUUCAGUAAGAAGAUGGAGUAGAUAUCAGAUAAAACAAUUCACGUUUAAUAUGUAAAUGUACCAAUUAUGUGAUUCAGUUUCAACUUUCAAGUACUUCCUGAGAGGUUAGUACAUUAUUAUUGAGCUCUCACAGAAAGCUUAAUCAUAGAUAUAAUUAACCUGAUCCAAAUGAGUAAAGUGGACCUUAGAAAGGCUAAGUGAUCUUUCUCUGGCUAUCCAGCUAGUAGUAAUGAAGUCAGGUCUUGAACCCCGGUUCUGCUGACUGAAUUGGAUGCACUAUAGUACAGGCUUUUAGCACCGAAGUGUGGUCCUCAGACCAGUGCCUGCCAACCAGAUGUUACUGGUCUGUGAGGAAAUAAGUACAGAUACUGACAGGAAGCUUUUAUAAACAAUUUAUUGGAGUGUUUUUGUUUCUGUUGGGUCUAAUUAAAAAAAUUGGAGCUUGUAUUUUAUGUGUCUUUGGUCUUAUUUUGUCUAGGAAUUCAUUUUUGCUGGGUUUUUUUUUUUCAACUGUAGUCCCACAACAGUCUGAAAAUAACCCAGUCACCAGAUAUCUUCCUCAAAUACAGAGGGAGAACUUUCUUUCACGCCUCCUUUAGCCUGUCGACUCCUUAUAAUAAUGCCUAAAUAUUCCAAAUUAAUACUGCCUCUUUAACCUGCUAAUUGUUUUCACAAUGUUACAAGAAAACUUGGAUCUGUGCAUUAUCACCAUCUAGUGGCUAAACUCAGGCAACACGAACUUCUACCAAACUCAGGAAAUUGCUCUGGAAAAACUACAGGAUUUUGGAUUUCCAGAACUGCCUUGAAGAGACAAAGAUUCUUGUACCAAGUUUUGGUCAACUGCAAAUCAAAGAACUUGGUUAUGCAGGGAAAACAAAUGAGGAUAUCUGUACCUGGAACUUUUAAACAAGAUUCUAAUAGUUAUGUGAAAAAAGCAUUCAAGAUUUUUGAGUAGGCACAGUGGCUUACGCCUGUAAUCCUAUCACUUUGCGAAACUGAGGUGGUGGAAGGAUCACUGAAGGUCGGGAGUUCAAGACCAGCCUGGCCAAUGUGGUGAAACCCCGUUUCUCCUAAAAUUAAAAAAAAAAAAAAAAAGCUAGGGGUGGUGGUCCAUGCCUGUAAUCCCAGCUACACGUGAGGCUAAGGCAGGAGAAUCACUUGAACCCAGGAGGCAGAGGUUGCAGUGAGCUGAGAUGGCGCCACUGCACUCCAGCCUGGGCGACAGAGCGAGACUCCGUCUCAAAAAAAAAGCAUUCAAGAUUUUUCAUUGUUCCUAAGAAUCUUAAUUAAAUGAAGACAGAAAGCAUCAUAAAGUCAGGUAACUACAGCACAGACAGCAUUAACAUUUACAAAAGUAUUUCUUAAGAAUUAAACCUGUCAGCUCUACUUACAAGAUGUAGAGCUUUCAGGUGAAGAUGAUUCAAGAACAUGCUUUCAAAAUAGUAGUUGAGAAACCAAAACAUAGCCACGCAGAAAUCUGCCAAUUAAGUUUUGCUGCCCUUUGAGCAAUAUGACUUAAUGUGAUUUACUUUAAUUAUAACUUAAGUACAACUUAAAUGCAGUUUCUAUUUUGCUAUUGUUAUAGAUGUAGGCUGGGUGCGGUGGCUUAUGCCUGUAAUCCUAACACAUACUUUGGGAGGCCAAGGUGGACGGAUCACUUGAGGUCAGGAGUUCGAGACCAGCCUGGCCAACAUGGUGAAACCCCGUCUCUACUGAAAAUACAAAAAUUAGCUGGUUGUGGUGGAGCAUGCCUGUAGUCCCAGCUACUUGGGAGGCUGAGGCAGGAGAAUCACUUGAAUCCAGGAGGUGGAGGUUCCCACGAGCCAAGAUCGCACCACUGCACUCCAGCCUGGCAACAGAGUGAGACUCCGUCUCAAAAAAAUGUUGUAGAUGUAUAAAAUUUAUACAUUUUUAGUCUGACUAGGGCUUUAGAGUGAAUAUAUCUCCUCAUUAAUCUGGCACAAAAUUAGUUAAGUAAGUAUACCCACAAAGUGUCAUCUAAUAUAUUGUUGCAUGUAGAGGAAAACACAGUGAAGAAACCUACUAACUUUAUUUGGAACCCUCAAUAUUGGUGGCUCCUUAAAAAUUGGAGAAAAAAAUCAAGUCUUAGGAAGUCUUAUCCAGUUUUAUGGUCUGCUGUGGUGGCACUUAAUGAAUUACCUGGAAUUAUAGUUCCUGUAAGAUGUUUUAUUUUUUAAAUAGUUGGCAGGCUAUACAAAGAGUGAUGUUCCAAAACUACACACAUGCUUUUUCCCUGUUCACAAAGGCAAACAGGCUGGCCAAAGUGUUUCCAGCAUCUUCGUCAUAUUUACCCUUUAUUAUCCAAGUGGUUUCCUGCUCUUCAAACCUUCCUUUCAAAAUUUUGUCUCCUACUUAAAACAAGUUAGGAUUAUUUAUCCUUUUAUUGGACUGAUUAUUCUAAGGAUAAGCUCUUACUUCACUUUCGGAGUAAAAGGCUUUGUGCCCUUUUUAAAGUUGGGUGUCAGCAAGCAGCUGGAAUUUUCCUGCCUGGUAAAAUUAAAACCAGCCCCACAAACUGGGGUUGGAGUCUGUGCAAAGCUCAUUACUAUCUAUGUGUGGGGUAGAAAUUAUAGUGUGUUAAAGGACCUAGUGUAAAAAAAAAAAAUUUUAAAGGACCUAGUGGAGGCUUGAACCUUCUUCACAUGAACGUCUUCCUUUCAGCCUAAAGUUCUUAAAAUGCACUAAAUUGACUUAAUCUUCAAUCAUACCUAUUUUUUCUGAUAUGGUUACAACAGCCCAAAUUACCAAGAUAAGUUGAAAGCCAGUAAAACAAUGAAAAUAAUUUCAAUAGUUGAAAAACUAUUCUAAUUUAUAUAAAGACAUUUAUCUCUAAAAAGACUGGUUGGGUUCAAGGACCCUUAAAGACUGAUUCUAUGUCUAAAUAAUCUGUUUUAUAAGUUCUCAUUCUGAAUGCAGAAAGAACCUAUUAUUUUCUGUAUAAAAAUUUAAAAAUUUAUAUUUCAUGGUAGGUUUUAAAUUUCCUAUUUCUUUAGGCAUCAGAGCUUAUUUCAAGAAUAGAUUCCAUG